AUCCCUCUGCAGAGCCCGGGGUCACCAGGAGGAGACGCCAUGACCCCCACCCUCGCAGCCCUGCUCUGCCUAGGGCUGAGUCUGGGCCCCAGGACCCACGUGCAGGCAGGGCCCUUCCCCAAACCCACCCUCUGGGCUGAGCCAGGCUCUGUGAUCAGCUGGGGGAGCCCCGUGACCAUCUGGUGUCAGGGGAGCCUGGAGGCCCAGGAGUACCGACUGGAUAAAGAGGGAAGCCCAGAGCCCUGGGACAGAAAUAACCCACUGGAACCCAAGAACAAGGCCAGAUUCUCCAUCCCAUCCAUAACAGAGCACCAUGCGGGGAGAUACCGCUGCCACUAUUACAGCUCUGCAGGCUGGUCAGAGCCCAGCGACCCCCUGGAGCUGGUGAUGACAGGAGCCUAUAGCAAACCCACCCUCUCAGCCCUGCCCAGCCCUGUGGUGGCCUCAGGGGGGAAUAUGACCCUCCAAUGUGGCUCACAGAAGGGAUAUCACCAUUUUGUUCUGAUGAAGGAAGGAGAACACCAGCUCCCCCGGACCCUGGACUCACAGCAGCUCCACAGUGGGGGGUUCCAGGCCCUGUUCCCUGUGGGCCCCGUGAACCCCAGCCACAGGUGGAGGUUCACAUGCUAUUACUAUUAUAUGAACACCCCCCGGGUGUGGUCCCACCCCAGUGACCCCCUGGAGAUUCUGCCCUCAGGCGUGUCUAGGAAGCCCUCCCUCCUGACCCUGCAGGGCCCUGUCCUGGCCCCUGGGCAGAGCCUGACCCUCCAGUGUGGCUCUGAUGUCGGCUACGACAGAUUUGUUCUGUAUAAGGAGGGGGAACGUGACUUCCUCCAGCGCCCUGGCCAGCAGCCCCAGGCUGGGCUCUCCCAGGCCAACUUCACCCUGGGCCCUGUGAGCCCCUCCCACGGGGGCCAGUACAGGUGCUAUGGUGCACACAACCUCUCCUCCGAGUGGUCGGCCCCCAGCGACCCCCUGAACAUCCUGAUGGCAGGACAGAUCUAUGACACCGUCUCCCUGUCAGCACAGCCGGGCCCCACAGUGGCCUCAGGAGAGAACGUGACCCUGCUGUGUCAGUCAUGGUGGCAGUUUGACACUUUCCUUCUGACCAAAGAAGGGGCAGCCCAUCCCCCACUGCGUCUGAGAUCAAUGUACGGAGCUCAUAAGUACCAGGCUGAAUUCCCCAUGAGUCCUGUGACCUCAGCCCACGCGGGGACCUACAGGUGCUACGGCUCAUACAGCUCCAACCCCCACCUGCUGUCUUUCCCCAGUGAGCCCCUGGAACUCAUGGUCUCAGGACACUCUGGAGGCUCCAGCCUCCCACCCACAGGGCCGCCCUCCACACCUGCCUCACACGCCAAGGAUUACACAGUGGAGAAUCUCAUCCGCAUGGGCAUGGCAGGCUUGGUCCUGGUGUUCCUCGGGAUUCUGUUAUUUGAGGCUCAGCACAGCCAGAGAAACCCCCAAGAUGCAGCCGGGAGGUGAACAGCGGAGAGGACAAUGCACCCUUCAGCGUGGUGGAGCCUCAGGGACAGAUCUGAUGAUCCCAGAAGGCUCUGGAGGACAAUCUAGGACCUCCAGAGGGGGGUGAGAUUUCAGGCCACACACUGUGGAAGGUAAUCAUGUCUGAUCACAAAUUUUGGGUCUCCACCUUACUUCCAAUCUAUGUUGUGAAUGCCCAGUUGAGACCCACGGAAAAGAGCUCAUGGGUGAGUGUGAAGUGCUUCUCUGUCUUAAGUUCCCAGAGAUCCUUGCCUCUUGGAGGCCAGCAAACACUAACUCUUGAGGAAUUCAUGACAAUAUCAUCUGAUUCCUCCUUCCCAGCUUGUAUGGCAGUCUCCCACCCUCAUGUGUUCAAUCUGAUGAUCCCAGGAGGUUCUGGAACAAAAUCUACAGCCUAUGCUUUCUGGACUAUCUGUCGAUCAUUCCUGAAGAGAGGGAUCAAUGUUGAGGUAUUCAUUUCACAUGAUGAAAAUGACAAUAUCAAAUGUCAGAGGUAGUAGGGCUCACGUAGAAAUCCAAUACAUCCAUGGUAGGACUGCAAAUUACUUGAAUCAAUUUGGGGAAAAUAUCAGAAGUACCCAGUGAAAAAGAAGAAACAUGGCCGGGCGCGGUGGCUCAUGCCUGUAAUCCCAGCACUUUGGGAGGCUGAGGCGGGCGGACACGAGUUCAGGAAUUCGAGUCCAGCUUGGCCAACAUAGUGAAACCCCGUCUCUACUAAAAAUACAAAACAUUAGCUGGGCGUGGUGGCAGGUGCCUGUAAUUUCAGCUACUCAGGAGGCUGAGGCAGGAGAAUUGCUUGAACCUGGGAGACGGAAGCAAGUUGGCGCCAGUUGGUGCAGUGAGCCAAGGUGGCGCCAUUGCACUCCGGCCCAGGUGACAGUACGAGACUUCAUCUAAAAAAAAAAGAAAAAAAAAAAGAAGAGACACACAGCUAUGAACACAAAGCACAGAACCUAGAGGAAAAUGUGUUCAUAUGGUGAGGUUUCAUUCACAACAACAUGGACAGGACUGCUGCUCAUAUUACACAACAGCCAUAAAACCCAAAAAUACAUCUAAAACAAAGGAAACAUAUGUGGUUCAAUUCCACCAAGGGAUACUACGAGGCCGUGCAGAGGCACAGACAAAAUCUACAAAGAGCAAUGCAAACCAACCUUCCAUCAUGAUGUUGAGUAAAGAAACAAGAGUAUAAAAAGAAGGUGUGCACAUGAAGCUCAAAAAGAGGCAGCAUUUAUUUUCUAGGGAGGCAAACUCAAAAUAGACCCCAUAAAUAAAGGAAAUAGAUUAUGUAAUCCAAAAUAGUGCUUGCACAUCAGGAAAUACUGGAGGGUUCUGUUCAACAUGGAAACUCCAAGGACCACUGGACGCGGGCACUGGAACGCUGACUUUCAUUUGGUGACCCUCAAUCCACUUCGAGUUAUUGGUAAAUCACAUAAUUUUAAUUUGAUACGGAAUAAUCAUACAUGUUUCUUGGGAGCAUGUGGUAAUCUGAUUCAUCCAUGCAAUGUGUAACGAUCCAAUAAAGGUUCCCAGGACAUUCAUCACCCUGAACAUUUGUUAUUAUGGUUAUUAUUUUGAGACAGAGUCUUGCACUGUCGCCCAGCUGGCGUGCAGUGGCAGGAUCUUGGCUCACUGCAAACUCUGCCUCCCGGGUUCAAGCAGUUUUCCUGUCUCAGCCUCCUGAGUAGCUAGGAUUACAGGCAUGCACCAUCACACCUCGCUAAUUUUUGUAUUUUUAUUACAGACGGGGUUUCACCAUGUUGCUCUGGCUGGUCUCGAACUCCUGACCUAAGGUGAUCCACCAGCGUCGGCUUUCCAUAGUGCUGGGAUUACAGGUGUGAGCCACUAUGCCUGGCCAACUUUUAUAAUUUCUGUGCUGGGAACAUUCCAAAUCUUCAUUUCUCACUCAUGUGGAAAAUACAAUAAUCUGUUGCUAACUAUGGUCACCCUACUGAGCUCUCAGGCCCUGGAACUUACUCCUUCUCUCCACCUGUAUUUCUGCACCCGUCCACCAACCUCUCUCCAUCCCUGUCCUCCACACUCCCUUGCCAGCCUCUGUUGACAACCAUUCUACUCUCUGCCAUCACAAGGCCCACUUUUGUAGCUUCCGCGUGAGUGAGAACAUGCUCCUCUUUCUGGGCCUGGCUUAUUUCACUGAACAUAAUGUCUUCCAGAUUCAUCUGUGUUGCUGAACAUGGUACAAUUUCCUUCUUUUUAUGCCUGAAUAUUAUUUCAUUGUGUAUAUAGACCACAUGUUCCUUAUCCAUUCAUCCAUUGAUGGACAUAGGUUGAUUCCAUAUCUUGGCUAUUGUGAAUACUGCUGCAAUAAACAUGGCAAUGCAGACACC